AGUUGCGCUUCUGGCGAUGGCGAUCAGAGGUCCUGCUGCGCUCUCCGCCGCGCUCUACCUCCAUUAGCCGCGCUGCGCGGUGCUGCGCCCUCGCCGGUGCCUCUCUCCUGGGUCCCAGGAUCGGCCCCCACCAUCCAGGCACGACCCCCUUCCCCGGCCCCUCGGCCUUUCCCCCAACUCGGCCAUCUCCGACCCGGGGCGCGUGUUCCCCCCGGCCCGGCGCCUUCUCUCCCUCCGGGGGCACCCGCUCCCUAGCCCCGGCCCGGCCCUCCCCGCGGCGCAGCACGGAGUCUCGGCGUCCCAUGGCGCAACCUACGGCCUCGGCCCAGAAGCUGGUGCGGCCGAUCCGCGCCGUGUGCCGCAUCCUGCAGAUCCCGGAGUCCGACCCCUCCAACCUGCGGCCCUAGAGCGCCCCCGCCGCCCCGGGGGAAGGAGAGCGCGAGCGCGCUGAGCAGACAGAGCGGGAGAACGCGUCCUCGCCCGCCGGCCGGGAGGCCCCGGAGCUGGCCCAUGGGGAGCAGGCGCCCGGUGCCGGCCACGACGACCGCCACCGCCCGCGCCGCGACCGGCCGGUGAAGCCCAGGGACCCCCCUCUGGGAGAGCCCCAUGAGGGCAGGAGAGUGAUGGAGAGUACGCCCAGCUUCCUGAAGGGCACCCCAACCUGGGAGAAGACGGCCCCAGAGAACGGCAUCGUGAGACAGGAGCCCGGCAGCCCGCCUCGAGAUGGACUGCACCAUGGGCCGCUGUGCCUGGGAGAGCCUGCUCCCUUUUGGAGGGGCGUCCUGAGCACCCCAGACUCCUGGCUUCCCCCUGGCUUCCCCCAGGGCCCCAAGGACAUGCUCCCACUUGUGGAGGGCGAGGGCCCCCAGAAUGGGGAGAGGAAGGUCAACUGGCUGGGCAGCAAAGAGGGACUGCGCUGGAAGGAGGCCAUGCUUACCCAUCCGCUGGCAUUCUGCGGGCCAGCGUGCCCACCUCGCUGUGGCCCCCUGAUGCCUGAGCAUAGUGGUGGCCAUCUCAAGAGUGACCCUGUGGCCUUCCGGCCCUGGCACUGCCCUUUCCUUCUGGAGACCAAGAUCCUGGAGCGAGCUCCCUUCUGGGUGCCCACCUGCUUGCCACCCUACCUAGUGUCUGGCCUGCCCCCAGAGCAUCCAUGUGACUGGCCCCUGACCCCGCACCCCUGGGUAUACUCCGGGGGCCAGCCCAAAGUGCCCUCUGCCUUCAGCUUAGGCAGCAAGGGCUUUUACUACAAGGAUCCGAGCAUUCCCAGGUUGGCAAAGGAGCCCUUGGCAGCUGCGGAACCUGGGUUGUUUGGCUUAAACUCUGGUGGGCACCUGCAGAGAGCCGGGGAGGCCGAACGCCCUUCACUGCACCAGAGGGAUGGAGAGAUGGGAGCUGGCCGGCAGCAGAAUCCUUGCCCGCUCUUCCUGGGGCAGCCAGACACUGUGCCCUGGACCUCCUGGCCCGCUUGUCCCCCAGGCCUUGUUCAUACUCUUGGCAACGUCUGGGCUGGGCCAGGCGAUGGGAACCUUGGGUACCAGCUGGGGCCACCAGCAACACCAAGGUGCCCCUCUCCUGAGCCGCCUGUCACCCAGCGGGGCUGCUGUUCAUCCUACCCACCCACUAAAGGUGGGGGUCUUGGCCCUUGUGGGAAGUGCCAGGAGGGCCUGGAGGGGGGUGCCAGUGGAGCCAGCGAACCCAGCGAGGAAGUGAACAAGGCCUCUGGCCCCAGGGCCUGUCCCCCCAGCCACCACACCAAGCUGAAGAAGACAUGGCUCACACGGCACUCGGAGCAGUUUGAAUGUCCACGCGGCUGCCCUGAGGUCGAGGAGAGGCCGGUUGCUCGGCUCCGGGCCCUCAAAAGGGCAGGCAGCCCCGAGGUCCAGGGAGCAAUGGGCAGUCCAGCCCCCAAGCGGCCACCGGACCCUUUUCCAGGCACUGCAGAACAGGGGGCUGGGGGUUGGCAGGAGGUGCGGGACACAUCGAUAGGGAACAAGGAUGUGGACUCGGGACAGCAUGAUGAGCAGAAAGGACCCCAAGAUGGCCAGGCCAGUCUCCAGGACCCGGGACUUCAGGACAUACCAUGCCUGGCUCUCCCUGCAAAACUGGCUCAAUGCCAAAGUUGUGCCCAGGCAGCUGGAGAGGGAGGAGGGCACGCCUGCCACUCUCAGCAAGUGCGGAGAUCGCCUCUGGGAGGGGAGCUGCAGCAGGAGGAAGACACAGCCACCAACUCCAGCUCUGAGGAAGGCCCAGGGUCCGGCCCUGACAGCCGGCUCAGCACAGGCCUCGCCAAGCACCUGCUCAGUGGUUUGGGGGACCGACUGUGCCGCCUGCUGCGGAGGGAGCGGGAGGCCCUGGCUUGGGCCCAGCGGGAAGGCCAAGGGCCAGCCGUGACAGAGGACAGCCCAGGCAUUCCACGCUGCUGCAGCCGUUGCCACCAUGGACUCUUCAACACCCACUGGCGAUGUCCCCGCUGCAGCCACCGGCUGUGUGUGGCCUGUGGUCGUGUGGCAGGCACUGGGCGGGCCAGGGAGAAAGCAGGCUUUCAGGAGCAGUCCGCGGAGGAGUGCACGCAGGAGGCCGGGCACGCUGCCUGUUCCCUGAUGCUGACCCAGUUUGUCUCCAGCCAGGCUUUGGCAGAGCUGAGCACUGCAAUGCACCAGGUCUGGGUCAAGUUUGAUAUCCGGGGGCACUGCCCCUGCCAAGCUGAUGCCCGGGUAUGGGCCCCCGGGGAUGCAGGCCAGCAGAAGGAAUCAACACAGAAAACGCCCCCAACUCCACAACCUUCCUGCAAUGGCGACACCCACAGGACCAAGAGCAUCAAAGAGGAGACCCCCGAUUCCGCUGAGACCCCAGCAGAGGACCGUGCUGGCCGAGGGCCCCUGCCUUGUCCUUCUCUCUGCGAACUGCUGGCUUCUACCGCGGUCAAACUCUGCUUGGGCCAUGAGCGAAUACACAUGGCCUUCGCCCCCGUCACUCCGGCCCUGCCCAGUGAUGACCGCAUCACCAACAUCCUGGACAGCAUUAUCGCACAGGUGGUGGAACGGAAGAUCCAGGAGAAAGCCCUGGGGCCGGGGCUUCGAGCUGGCCCGGGUCUGCGCAAGGGCCUGGGCCUGCCCCUCUCUCCAGUGCGGCCCCGGCUGCCUCCCCCAGGGGCUUUGCUGUGGCUGCAGGAGCCCCAGCCUUGCCCUCGGCGUGGCUUCCACCUCUUCCAGGAGCACUGGAGGCAGGGCCAGCCUGUGUUGGUGUCAGGGAUCCAAAGGACAUUGCAGGGCAACCUGUGGGGGACAGAAGCUCUUGGGGCACUUGGAGGCCAGGUGCAGGCGCUGAGCCCCCUCGGACCUCCCCAGCCCAGCAGCCUGGGCAGCACAACAUUCUGGGAGGGCUUCUCCUGGCCUGAGCUUCGCCCAAAGUCAGACGAGGGCUCUGUCCUCCUGCUGCACCGAGCUUUGGGGGAUGAGGACACCAGCAGGGUGGAGAACCUAGCUGCCAGUCUGCCACUUCCGGAGUACUGCGCCCUCCAUGGAAAACUCAACCUGGCUUCCUACCUCCCACCGGGCCUUGCCCUGCGUCCACUGGAGCCCCAGCUCUGGGCAGCCUAUGGUGUGAGCCCGCACCGGGGACACCUGGGGACCAAGAACCUCUGUGUGGAGGUGGCCGACCUGGUCAGCAUCCUGGUGCAUGCCGACACACCACUGCCUGCCUGGCACCGGGCACAGAAAGACUUCCUUUCAGGCCUGGACGGGGAGGGGCUCUGGUCUCCGGGCAGCCAGGUCAGCACUGUGUGGCACGUGUUCCGGGCACAGGACGCCCAGCGCAUCCGCCGCUUUCUCCAGAUGGUGUGCCCGGCCGGGGCAGGCGCCCUGGAGCCUGGCGCCCCAGGCAGCUGCUACCUGGAUGCAGGGCUGCGGCGGCGCCUGCGGGAGGAGUGGGGCGUGAGCUGCUGGACCCUGCUCCAGGCCCCCGGAGAGGCCGUGCUGGUGCCUGCAGGGGCUCCCCACCAGGUGCAGGGCCUGGUGAGCACAGUCAGCGUCACUCAGCACUUCCUCUCCCCUGAGACCUCUGCCCUCUCUGCUCAGCUCUGCCACCAGGGACCCAGCCUUCCCCCUGACUGCCACCUGCUUUAUGCCCAGAUGGACUGGGCUGUGUUCCAAGCAGUGAAGGUGGCCGUGGGGACAUUACAGGAGGCCAAAUAGAGGGAUGCUAGGUGUCUGGGAUCGGGGUGGGGACAGGUAGACCAGGUGCUCAGCCCAGGCACAACUUCAGCAGGGGAUGGCGCUAGGGGACUUGGGGAUUUCUGGUCAACCCCACAAGCACCACUCUGGGCACAAGCAGGGCACUCUGUUCCCCUCCCCCUUAAGCCAACAACCACAGUGCCACCAAGCUCACACCUGUCCUUCUCAGGCUGGCAUCUCCCCCACCCUGUGCCCCUUUUCAUGGUACCAGGCCCGCACUGGGGGCAAUUGACUUCCUCCAAUCCCCACUCCUCCGAGACCCAGGAGACAAACAGCCCUUCCUUGGGGAAACUUGGGAAUCAUUCUGGCUUAAACAACACCUCCUCCUGCUGCUCACUCCCGCUGAGCCCACUCUACUGCCCCAGCUCCGUUUCUACCACCGCAUCCUCACUGGGCUCACUGCAGGCAUGCUGAACAAGGGGCCUCCAACCUUCUGCCCUCCUGCCAAAAGAUCUGGGGAGUGUGAGGAGAGGGUGGCAUCAGGAGCUGCUCAGGCUUGGCGGAGGGAGCGGCAUGGGCGAUGUCACUCAGCCCCUUCCCGGUCCGCCCGCUUCCCUCCUUCAUGAUUUCCAUUAAAGUCUGUUGUUUUGUGACUGCUGCCAGUGUGGUUGGCCCUGCCCCUGCAGGCCACAUGGUCCAGGGAGGGAGGGGGACAUGGAAAUCUGCCUUAGAGACAAAUGGAGUAGGGCAGCCCGGAGCUGGGGCCCAAGGGACAGGACACCACUGCCUGCUCUUCGUCUGGGGCCUGGGGCCUUGCCUCCCACUGAGGAGACUUUGGGUGGGGUGGGGGGCUGUCCCCCAAAGAUGCUCCUGAGUGCAAGAGCAGGCAAGGCAGAGUCCUGGGGCACAGCCACGAGGUGACCUCCCUGUGCAGAGACUCCCGAGCCCUACUCCACCCAGCAAGCUCCAGUCCGCCCCAUCUCUCCCGUCUACCCUGACCUGGAGAUCCAGAAGUAUGGCCCAGAAGAGCCCUUGCCCCGCCUGUCUGCCCUUGGUGGCAGUGGCCAUGGCCGACGCCAGGCCCAGCCACCCUGGGACUGAGCCUGACUGCUUCAGACAGCCGACCCCUCCUUGUCCCCGCUCCACGCCCGCAGCCUCCUGGUGGCGCUCCGCCCUCUCCCGCUUCCUUUGUGUAUCUCAGCCCUACAAAGAAAAACACUCCCACUCUUGUCAUACCUAAUUGUUCCUGCUGUGGUUUGGGGAAUUUUUUUUAUUAAAUAAAGUUUUUUAUUAUAAGGGUAA